AGUAGAGGCUGUGGGAGAGAGCGCGAUGGGCCGCGGCGGUGGGCGCACGUUCCGCGGGGACUCAUGCCACGCGCGUCCCGGCCCGACGCGCAAUUAGCAGCCACCUCCGCAGCCCGCCGCCACCGCCUCCCUGCCCUCCCGGGCUGCCGCAGCUAGGAGCUCCAGCCGUCGCCUCGCGCAGGCUGCGGGCAUUGUCCUCUCGGUUCGCCGCCCGGGCUGCUGCUGCCGCCGCGGACUGCUGCGGGGCCCGGACCCGCACCCCAGGGAUACGCUGCCGCCGCCGCCGGCCGGCCCGGCGCCCGGCCUCCGUUCGGUGGUUUCCGCCCUGCGUUCUCUGGGUUGCUCUCUCCUGGGUUUUUCCUGCGUAGCUGAGGAAGGGGAAGAGAAGUCCAGCCGCCAAGCCCAGCCUUCCCCGGCGCGCAGCCCCGACGGGGCCGCGGCAGGCGCGGCGAGAGCGCUGACGGAGCCAUGAGAGAGUACAAAGUGGUGGUGCUGGGCUCGGGCGGCGUGGGCAAGUCCGCGCUCACCGUGCAGUUCGUGACGGGCUCCUUCAUCGAGAAGUACGACCCGACCAUCGAAGACUUUUACCGCAAGGAGAUUGAGGUGGACUCGUCGCCGUCGGUGCUGGAGAUCCUGGAUACGGCGGGCACCGAGCAGUUCGCGUCCAUGCGGGACCUGUACAUCAAGAACGGCCAGGGCUUCAUCCUGGUCUACAGCCUCGUCAACCAGCAGAGCUUCCAGGACAUCAAGCCCAUGCGGGACCAGAUCAUCCGCGUGAAGCGGUACGAGCGCGUGCCCAUGAUCCUGGUGGGCAACAAGGUGGACCUGGAGGGUGAGCGCGAGGUCUCGUACGGGGAGGGCAAGGCCCUGGCUGAGGAGUGGAGCUGCCCCUUCAUGGAGACGUCGGCCAAAAACAAAGCCUCGGUAGACGAGCUAUUUGCCGAGAUCGUGCGGCAGAUGAACUACGCGGCGCAGCCCAACGGCGAUGAGGGCUGCUGCUCGGCCUGCGUGAUCCUCUGAGGCGGCCACCGCGCGCCGGCCGCGCUCUGCGCACAAAAGCCAAACGCAUCCGACUCUCUAAAUGUGAUUUAUUUCUUGCUUUGAGAUUGGAGACCACUUUGCAUUGGCCAGGGUGUCUUGGGAGCCCGGCUGGCCUCCGCGGCCGGCGUCCCCUGCCUCCACCCUGUGCCCGAGGGGGUGUCCGGUCCUGCCCAUCCGAUACUCUGGUGGAAAUGUGGCUCUUUGCAGCAUGUACGUUUCUCCCUGAUUUUGGUUGAUGCAUAUUUCCCCGUUUAAGUAGCCGUUAGGGCGCAGUAUCGGCAGCUUGACACCCACCAAGCAAAAGUUUCAGCCUGGAAAAAAAAUGGGGGGGAAGGGUGGAUGAAAAGGAGGGAGAGAAGGUGGAAAUGGUUUUUUUUUUUUUUUUUCUAUUUUCUUUCUUUUUUUUUUUUUUUUUUUUUGGUCAACAGCCGUUUUUCUAGUUCCAAGUUUUAAAUACAUGGAAGGAAGUCCGGGAGAACCAUAUGAAGGAGCAGGAGGAGAGGAAGAAACUUUUUUUCCUUCUUUUCCAGGAGUAGCUGGAAAUUAAGAUCGGGUUCCUUUUCUGCCAGCUUGGAAGGGCAACCCCAUGACUGAUUGCGAUUCUGAGGAUGUCUAUGCAAAGUUGGAUUCUUGUUACAGUGUAUCCAAUCUGAAGUAUUGCACAUCUGAACUGGGACUGUUAACACUGAUGCCAAUACAGUGUGGGGUGCCAGAAAGUGUCUGCUGAUAUUUGUGGAAAAAAAAUCUAUUUUGUUUACCUACUGUAUCAAAGGGGAGUCUGGGGGAGAAUGGUAGUAUUUUUUUUUUUUAUCAGCUGUGAAAAAAAUGUUACAGAUCUGCACAUUUUCGUGUGUACUAUGGUGUGUGUGUGUAUGUGUGUGGUGUGUGUGUGUUUUAAGUUUAGCCUUUUGUUUUUGUUUUUUGGUUGGCAGUAACCGAUUUUAAUGACUAGCUUUUAAAAAUACAGUACAAAGACUUUGUAAAUGUGAUUCAGGGCCCCCAGCACCCCUGUGUCUGCAGAGUGCCUUCAAAACUCAGCUGUUCCAGCCGGUGCCAACCUGUGAACUUCCCACCAUAUCCCAGAAUCUGCUAUUCCCCAAACCACUUCCCAGUUUCCUUUCAGUAAUCUUUCUGAAGGAGCCAGGACAAUAGGGCCUGUUGUUUAGUGAAUUUCUUUAUUAUUUUCAGCCUUUAAAAUGUAAUUUCCAUCUCUUGCAAUGAAUUUGUUUCCCUUUUUUUUGCUUCAUUUUGUUUAAAUUUUCAGGUAUUUAGCUCCCCUUUCAUAUUAUUUUUAAAUUUUUUAAUUACCUGUUGUAGGGUGUUCCUCCAGAAGCAAAGAGCAAAAUUUUACUGUUGUGAUGUACCAAUUCUAACUAAUUGUAAUUUUUAAUUUCAUGCGUUUAAUCAUUGUCUCUUCAUUUUAAGACUUUUAAUACAAAUGUCAUUUUUAAAGAAACAAACCCAAAACUAUUGUUUGUGUUUCUGUGUUUCAUAUUCAGUGAUUUAAUACAGUAUCAUGGCUGAGGUGGAUGGGGCAGGUGCAUGAUACUCUUCAGAGCUAUUUGUGAAAUUUUAAAGACAGAAGUGUCUCAGUGACAAGUUGGAUGACACUACUCCCAACUUUUUAAAUUUGGAGAAAACCAUCAAGGUCGAGGAAGCCCUGGGUAUGGCCAUUACCAUCUGAUUAGAAGAUGAACAGGUAUUUUGAAUCUGAUCUGACAUGGAACAGUUUACCUCAUUGUAGGUAGGGAACAAGAGAACCCAUCUAUUAAAAUUGCCUUAGAUCUGGGAAAGUAACCAUCCUUCUGGCAAAGUAGGAUGGCACUUUUAAGUUUUUCUUCCUUUUUUCCCUCUGUUUAUAUUGCACAUCAAGUCAAAAACAUGUUUGGGAAAGAUGGUUUUCAAUUCUGAAGUUAUACCUAGUGAUGUUUUUUGCAGUACAUUUGAAUGGAUUGUAGACACUGCCUCAACCCUUUUGAGGUUUUGAUUUGGAAAUAGAUUUAAAAGAAAACAGGCUAAGAUAAUAUCCUUGUUCUCAUUUACACCCUGCAGUUUGGACCACAUUUGACCUCAUAAGUUUUUCCUUUUAACAGUAGGAGGCAGUGUGAGCUUUUUAUUUUUUAUUUUUCUUAAGGUGGUCUUAGUAAUAUAACAUGUUCAUACAUAUCAAGAGAGUACUUGGUAUACCUUAGGUCUAUGAAGUGUAGCUGAAAUCUGAAGAGUCUUGACAAAGGGAUUUACACCCUUGACAAAACCAAAAGAAAUUAACAGGCCACAGGUUUCUUUAAAGCUGUGUUAACAUAUCUUGCCUUAAAAUGUGUGUGUGUGUUUUUGCUUUGCUUUUUUUUUUUUGCCCAAGAGGCAUCUCAGUACUCCAGCAAUGGAGGAAGAAUAGAGAAUUUUGCCUGGCAAUGGUCCUACUGCCAUUUUUUUUUUCCCACUCUGAUCUCACUUAAGUUUGAUAUCAAACACAAUUGGGAGGCAAUAGUAUCAAUAUCCUAAAUGUAGAAAUUAAAAGAUACUGUAUAAUUUUAUGCCUUUGCAAAGAUUCGUUCUUGUAUUUGAAUAAAUUCAGUUGCUAAAGUAGAUCCAAAGUGUUAAAAAUGCUGAAGUCAUGUCAAGUACUGUCUGGAGGGUUUUUUUAAGAAAAGGCAUUUGGCAUUUAACUGUCUCUUGUUUUAUUUUUAAGUUUUUGGAAACCUUUUGACAUAAAAUGCUGCCAAGUAUCUAAGAAAUGUAUAUACUGACAGAAGAUAUUUGAAAGUGGAAAAUUGGAAAUGAAAUAUGUUGCUGGGUGCGUUAAUCACCUCCGCCCAGGAUUUAGUCACUUGCAGGACCUCUUUAUAGUCUAGGAUGGCAGAGCAGAAGAUUUUAAUAUGCUUUUAUUAAGUGAUGUAAAAUAAAUGCUUUUUGGAUUAUCAAUGAAAGCAAUUUUAUGUGUGCCUGAAGCAAGAAAAUAGCGUUUUUGGUUUUAUCUCAUAUUUUCUUGGCAAAAUUGAGAGAAAUUAGGAACACUGCUAUUUUUUUCUUAAAAAUGUUUUUAAGAAUAUGUUCGUUUCUUUGACUAUUAAGAACCCCUUGUGGUAUUAGUGUGUGAAGAGAUAAGGGCAUUUGUUUCAAUGAAAAAGUUAGUGUUAAAGGAAGUGAGUCAGGGAGGGCGGAGUUUGUUGUAAGGCAAUCACCUGUCAAAACAGAAAUUGGGUGGGAAAGGAGUCUUUAUCUUGGGGAGCAAAAGCUGACUUUUAAACUUGACCCCUGCUGUUUUUAAACAGCUUUUCCUUUUGGUCUCUGACAGUCAAUCCAGGUUUUAUGUUAUUUCAAAAGGGUUAUUUUUGUCCUCCUUUUUUAAUAGCUUCAGGAAAGUUAAAGGUAUCAUCUUAGGUCUAACACUCUAGUCUUUGAGAGUUACGGUUCUUUCGUAGAACAAUUUCCAUGUUGUUAACUGUUGUAGACUUAAUUGAAUCACAUUUUGGGACCAGAUGUAUUUGGGGAUAGAAUUCUUUAAAUGUAUGGGACUUCAUGCUUCCUGAUUAUGUAAUAUUUCCUGUGGUUGGGAAUCCUAGAAUGCCUGAUCUAUUUUAUCUGUUCAGGUAGUUUUGUUAUUGUACCCUCUUUUGGGUCAUAUUCUAGUAUUUCUCACAGGGGGUAUGAGAAACAGAAAGCUAUAUGUAGCAGCUGGUCUUGAGAAGUAGAAGCAUCUUAACUGUCAUAAGAGCAUAGAUUUUUUGUUUUUCACAACAGCUGGAAUAAGUUCCUGCAUUAUAAGUAUAAAGGGAACCGAGAUUUAAUUUGGAGAUCAUCACUGUUAAAACGAUACCAGACAUUUGUCACAGUGUCUUAUUUGGGGAAAGUUUGCUAAUAUACAUUUUGUCUGUGAAAAUAUAGUAAAUUUUAAAAUACUAAUAUAAUGUGGUAUUCUUGAUUACAGUAUUUUAUGCAGACUAUUAGGAAUGAUUCAGUGCAUUUAACUGAACACAGAGCUAGUUCUAGGUGAGUGAGAUCUUUAUCUAUUAACUGGAUUUUGAAGGUUUGAGAAGGCUAUGGGGAUCAUCUGGUUGAAAGGUUCUCAAACUUGACCAUAUAUCAAAAUCACCUGGAGCUUAAAACAUGUACUGCUGGGACCCUCCUCCAGUUUCUUACCCAGUGGGUCUCGGGUAGGGUCUCAAUUUUCAUUUCUAACAAGUUUCCAAGUGAUUGUGUUAUUGCUGUUCCAGGGACCACACUUUGAAAACCAGUGAUCUAGACUGAACUCCAAAUGAGUACUAUACUGACAGCCACCUAGAUAUUGAGAGACACAGACUUCAGACUCAUGUCACACAUUUUGGAGUGCUGUCUACUACAGUUAGAGAAUAAUCUCUAUUGAAAUCUAAGCUAAAGAGGACAUAUACCAUUUAUACUAAGACUAACUGUUGUGUGUGAAAUAGAAUAAACAUUGCAGGUAGUUUUUGAUCAUUUUCACAUUAUUACAGGAACAUUUUGACUAUGGUUUUCAAUGUUAAUUCAGAAGUUGACUUUAAAUGAAAAUGUGGUUAGAAUAGAGGCAAAGCCUAAGUGAUCAGAAUCAACAUUCCCCUUCUCCCCAACCUAGGGGAAAAAAAAUUUGAAAAGUAUGUCUUCAAUAAAAGGGGACACUUUAUUUGUCUUCUCUUCAACAUUAAAAAACAAAGAUUUUAAGUUUUCAUGGCAAGGGUUCUAAAAAUCAUUGUGCCAGAGAAUUUAAAUCUUCAUAUCAUGGUAAGCACAUGCGUAUGUCUGUGACUCAGUUUCUUAGCCAGACUUCCAGGUGUUAGUUAAUUCCUUCUCAUUUAGUUCUACUGUAAUCCAUUCUGGGAAAAUGCAUACCACAAAACUGUGUAUCUUGCAGCUUCUUUCGUUAUGCAUCUUAAUUCCCUCAGAAGGUCCCAGAACUUUAUGUUAAAGAUCUGGGUUUUUAAAGACAAUUUGGGGGCCUUCUAAAGAAACAAUAGUAGAUCUAAUUACAAGUAGUGGAUUGCUUACUUCAAAUUUCUCUUUUACAAUUUAGAAAGUUUAGUACCAGUUUAUAGACUGAGGGAGUAGUAGCUACUAUUUAGAUGCUGAGAAUAAUAUUAUCAUGCUUGGGUGGGGAAGAAAGGCCCUUACUCAAAUCUCCAUUUUCAUUUUUAAUGCUUCCUGGACUUCAGUUAUUUUCUUGCUUUUGCCUCAAGAAUAAUAAAUAUUUUUGGUUAAAAUUUUUUUUGUUCAACCCUGUUGUUGUUACUGUUAUUUUCAUAGCACAGUAGUCUACAGCUCUCUAUAGUAGCUUAAUAGCUAUUUGCUGAAUGAAUGGAACAUGGAGUGUUACAUCUGAAACUAUUCUAUUAGAAGGUGAAAAGUGUUGAUUGAAGAAUGGUAGGAUUUUAUCUUCCCUACCCAUGAUAGAUUUAUUAAGAUUGUCUUUGGAGCUAUGUCUUCCAUUCCAACUAUACAGAAAUAAACUUUUUUAAAGUUUAGUUUGCCCAUCUGAUAAAGGAACAUUCCUGUAUGCUAUUCUAAGGUUCAUUUUCAACAAAAGUUACAGACAUUUAUGGUUGAUAGUUUGAGAUCUAUGACAGUUUUAGGGAGCUCCAUAUUCAAAAGGCUAUUGCUGGUGAUAGUACAAUGAAACACUGACUUCAGUAUAUUUUUAUCUUGGCUUUCAUUUUACGGUUAUUUCUACUACUGUUAAUAUGGACUAAUACUUGAUUUUGUGAACCUGUUUUAAUUUUAGGGUUAUAUUUAUGUUGGAAUAAUAUAUUUUAAAAGUGUCCUAUACUAUGAAUUUAUUUGCCAUAUAUAAGACAAUCAGAAUUAUCUGGUAGUUUAUUCUAAUCCUGGUUAAUAAUCAUUAGGACUAAACUAUUUACAUUAAAGAAGGAAAAAACAAUGAGAUGAUAAUUUUUUUUUUCUUUGAGACGGAGUCUUGCUCUGUCGGCCAGGCUGGAGUGCAAUGGCGCGAUCUCGGCUCACUGCAACUUCCGCUUCCUGGGUUCAAGCAAUUCUCCUGCCUCAGCCUUUCCAGUAGCUGGGACUACGGGCGCCCUCCACCACUCCCGGCUAAUUUUUGUAUUUUUCAUAGAGACAGCAUUUCACCAUACUGGCCAGGCUGGUCGUGAACUCCUGACCUUGUGAUCUGCCCACCUUGGCUUCCCAAAGUGCUGGGAUUACAGGUGUGAGCCACCGCACCCAGCCUUUUUUUUGAAAUGGAGUCUGGCUCUGUCGCCCAGGCUGGAGUGCAAUGGCGCGAUCUCGGCUCACUGCAACCUCUGCCUCCCAGGUUCAAGCGAUUAGCCUGCCUCAUCCUCCUGAGUAGCUGGGAUUACAGGCGUGCACCACCACGCCCGCCUAAUUUUUGUAUUUUUAGUAGAGAUGGGGUUUCACUACGUUGGUCAGGAUGGUCUUGAACUUCUGACCUUGUGCUCCACCCACCUCAGCCUCCCAAGAGUUGGGAUUACAGGCGUGAGCCACUGCACCCGGCUGAGAUGAUAAUUUUAUUUAAAAAAAAAAUUGUAGAGAUAGGGUCUUGCCGUGUUGCCCAGGCUGGUCUCAAAUUCCUGGGCUCAGGAGAUCUUCCCUCCUCAGCCCCUCAAAGUGCUGGGAUUACAGGCCUGAGCCACUGCAUCCAGCCAGGAGUGACAAUUUCUAAAGCCUUAAUUAGUGAAAUGGUUUGUUUUGAGAAGCAGAAAUGACUAAGUGGUAUAGACAUGCAGGAAAAGCAAAAUGGGCCUUAUGGCUAUUGAAAUUAUGAGUGUUGAUCUGUUCUAUAAAUUGGAGGAGACAGCUAUUUGCAUUCUUUCUUAUCCAGUUGACUAAACUUACUCAUUUUAAAAUGAAUUAUCUUGCAAAAUUAUGUGAGGUUAAGUUUGUCAGAGGAUUGAAAACGUGGUUGGUUUAUUUGUGGUAAUUGUGAAAAAUUGCAAAGGUAGCAAAAUUUUUUAAAAAAUGGAAAAGAGAAAGAUUAUUGAUGCCUUGUGAAUACAGGUGUCCCCAAAAGGCCUGAGACCAACCUUAAUUAUCAAGAAUAUGGUUGCAGUGGAAAUUGGUAAACAGCUGAAAUUGAUUCAUUGAUUAUUCAACACUUAUUGAGCACAUACUACUAUUAUUAAUAGCUGUACUGCGAGCGCUAAUACUUAAAAGAGGAAGUCAGGUGAAGGCGCAACAGCUUUAUGCUCUUUUUCACUAUAAUCUGUGAAAUAGUGUAUAUUAAACAAUAAUAGUAUAUGGAAAAGCACAUCUACAUGUGUCAUCAGUUAUAAUACUGUGGGGCUGUUUGGCAGACAAUAGAGUAGAUAAAUUUAUUGAACAUUGGGCCUUUGAAAGGUAUGUGGAAAUUGUAAAUAAAAAUGGAUUCCAUGAAUUUCAAA